UCAAUAGCGGCCCUGGCCUCCUCCCUCUGCUCUCUGUAACAUAACAGGCUGGCAGCGCCCAGAGAGGAUUUUGACUAUUCCAGUUUUAGUAAAAGGCUGGGGGAAAUCCAUAUAAGCAAGUCUAUUGUUCUUGGGGAGAAAAAGAGUAUGACUUUGGUGUAGAGAAAAGAGGACAGAAUCUGCAGAGGGACAGGUAGGAGGCAGGAUGACAGUCCUGGAGAAUGCCACAGGUGGAGGCCAGAACAUGGUGGAUCCGGGCAAAUCUGAGCUGACAGUGGGCCAGGAUGAGCUGCCUCGCAGGGAAGGUGCAGCCCAACCCCAGCUUCCCAGGAAAGACUUCCCCCUGAGUUCUUCUCAACUCAUCUCUGCAGACCGGCUUGCUCUACUCUUCCUUUAUCAUGGCAGAAUGUGCUUGGCUCCCAGGCUGACAUGGUGCAGAUGCAGCCACACAUACCAACUGACUCACAAUCCGUCAGGGGCCCAAACUCAAGCUUUCAGGUCUCAGCUCAAAUACCACCUCCUUGGAGAAAUCUCUGCUGACCACACUUGCUGAACUGACAGCCAGCUCCUCCCCUGCCCUUCUCUGAUAUGGGAUGAAUUGUGUCCCUCUCUCUUUGCAAAAACAUUUAUGUCAGUACCAUCCGAGCCCCGGAUACGUCAGAAUGUGACUGUUUUUGGAGAUAGGGCCUUUAAGGGGGCAAUUAAGUUAAAAUGAGGUCUUAAUCUAAUACGAAUGUGUCCUUCUAACAAGAGGAGAUUAGGACACAGACAGGCAUAUAAGAAAGACCAUGUGAAGAUAUAGAGAGACGUAAAAGCCAAGGAGAGAGGCCUCAGAAGAAACCCACCCUUCCAACAUCUGAUCUUGGACUUCUGGCCUCCAGAAUUGGGAGAAAAUAAAUUUCUGUUAUUUAAGUUA